AUUGCUGCUGGAGGGACAGGGGCAGGGGGAUCCCUCAGACCCAGGCCGGUGCGUCCCCUCGACCCCCUCAGCCCUUCUCUCAAGCCCCAGUUUCCUUAGGCCCCUGCCCAGAUGCACCUGAACAGCGUCCCCAUGACCAGCCCCCCCGGCCCCCCCUCAGCCCUGCCCCCUCACCCCACUCCAGGCUGGUACCUGUUCCAGUUCCACCGGCUCCUGCAGUACGCACGGCCCAAGCCAGGCAGCCCCAGGCCCUUCUUCUGGAUGUUCGUGGACAAUCUGGUGCUGAACAAGGAAGACCUGGACGUCGCAUCUCGCUUCCUGGAGAUGGAGCCAGUCACCAUCCCAGAUGUCCACGGCGGAUCCUUGCAGAAUGCUGUCCGCGUGUGGAGCAACAUCCCAGCCAUAAGGAGCAGCAGGCACUGGGCUCUGGUUUCGGAAGAAGAAUUGUCCCUGCUGGCCCAGAACAAGCAGAGCUCGAAGCUCGCGGCCAAGUGGCCCACCAAGCUGGUGAAGAACUGCUUUCUCCCCCUAAGAGAAUAUUUCAAGUAUUUUUCAACAGAACUCACUUCCUCUUUAUAAAUGAGUCACUAUACUGUGAAGAAAAAGACUUUUCCUAGAACAAAGGCAACUUUCCUCA